AUCUAUCCUUUACGGCAAGGGUACCUACGGUACCUGAAAACAACGAUGGCAUGGAAAACACUUCCCAUUUACCUGUUGUUGCUGCUGUCUGUUUUCGUGAUUCAGCAAGUUUCAUCUCAAGAUUUAUCAAGCUGUGCAGGGAGAUGUGGGGAAGGGUAUUCUAGAGAUGCCACCUGCAACUGUGAUUAUAACUGUCAACACUACAUGGAGUGCUGCCCUGAUUUCAAGAGAGUCUGCACUGCGGAGCUUUCCUGUAAAGGCCGCUGCUUUGAGUCCUUCGAGAGAGGGAGGGAGUGUGACUGCGACGCCCAAUGUAAGAAGUAUGACAAGUGCUGUCCCGAUUAUGAGAGUUUCUGUGCAGAAGUGCAUAAUCCCACAUCACCACCAUCUUCAAAGAAAGCACCUCCACCUUCAGGAGCAUCUCAAACCAUCAAAUCAACAACCAAACGUUCACCCAAACCACCAAACAAGAAGAAGACUAAGAAAGUUAUAGAAUCAGAGGAAAUAACAGAAGAACAUUCUGUUUCUGAAAAUCAAGAGUCCUCCUCCUCCUCCUCCUCUUCCUCUUCUUCUUCAACAAUUCGGAAAAUCAAGUCUUCCAAAAAUUCAGCUGCUAAUAGAGAAUUACAGAAGAAACUCAAAGUAAAAGAUAACAAGAAGAACAGAACUAAAAAGAAACCUACCCCCAAACCACCAGUUGUAGAUGAAGCUGGAAGUGGAUUGGACAAUGGUGACUUCAAGGUCACAACUCCUGACACGUCUACCACCCAACACAAUAAAGUCAGCACAUCUCCCAAGAUCACAACAGCAAAACCAAUAAAUCCCAGACCCAGUCUUCCACCUAAUUCUGAUACAUCUAAAGAGACGUCUUUGACAGUGAAUAAAGAGACAACAGUUGAAACUAAAGAAACUACUACAACAAAUAAACAGACUUCAACUGAUGGAAAAGAGAAGACUACUUCCGCUAAAGAGACACAAAGUAUAGAGAAAACAUCUGCUAAAGAUUUAGCACCCACAUCUAAAGUGCUGGCUAAACCUACACCCAAAGCUGAAACUACAACCAAAGGCCCUGCUCUCACCACUCCCAAGGAGCCCACGCCCACCACUCCCAAGGAGCCUGCAUCUACCACACCCAAAGAGCCCACACCUACCACCAUCAAGUCUGCACCCACCACCCCCAAGGAGCCUGCACCCACCACCACCAAGUCUGCACCCACCACUCCCAAGGAGCCUGCACCCACCACCACCAAGGAGCCUGCACCCACCACUCCCAAGGAGCCUGCACCCACCACCACCAAGGAGCCUGCACCCACCACCACCAAGUCUGCACCCACCACUCCCAAGGAGCCUGCACCCACCACCCCCAAGAAGCCUGCCCCAACUACCCCCAAGGAGCCUGCACCCACCACUCCCAAGGAGCCUACACCCACCACUCCCAAGGAGCCUGCACCCACCACCAAGGAGCCUGCACCCACCACUCCCAAAGAGCCUGCACCCACUGCCCCCAAGAAGCCUGCCCCAACUACCCCCAAGGAGCCUGCACCCACCACUCCCAAGGAGCCUGCACCCACCACCACCAAGGAGCCUUCACCCACCACUCCCAAGGAGCCUGCACCCACCACCACCAAGUCUGCACCCACCACUACCAAGGAGCCUGCACCCACCACUACCAAGUCUGCACCCACCACUCCCAAGGAGCCUUCACCCACCACCACCAAGGAGCCUGCACCCACCACUCCCAAGGAGCCUGCACCCACCACCCCCAAGAAGCCUGCCCCAACUACCCCCAAGGAGCCUGCACCCACCACUCCCAAGGAACCUGCACCCACCACCACCAAGAAGCCUGCACCCACCACUCCCAAAGAGCCUGCCCCAACUACCCCCAAGGAGACUGCACCCACCACCCCCAAGAAGCUCACGCCCACCACCCCCGAGAAGCUCGCACCCACCACCCCUGAGAAGCCCGCACCCACCACCCCUGAGGAGCUCGCACCCACCACCCCUGAGGAGCCCACACCCACCACCCCUGAGGAGCCUGCUCCCACCACUCCCAAGGCAGCGGCUCCCAACACCCCUAAGGAGCCUGCUCCAACUACCCCUAAGGAGCCUGCUCCAACUACCCCUAAGGAGCCUGCUCCAACUACCCCUAAGGAGACUGCUCCAACUACCCCUAAAGGGACUGCUCCAACUACCCUCAAGGAACCUGCACCCACUACUCCCAAGAAGCCUGCCCCCAAGGAGCUUGCACCCACCACCACCAAGGAGCCCACAUCCACCACCUCUGACAAGCCCGCUCCAACUACCCCUAAGGGGACUGCUCCAACUACCCCUAAGGAGCCUGCUCCAACUACCCCUAAGGAGCCUGCUCCAACUACCCCUAAGGGGACUGCUCCAACUACCCUCAAGGAACCUGCACCCACUACUCCCAAGAAGCCUGCCCCCAAGGAGCUUGCACCCACCACCACCAAGGGGCCCACAUCCACCACCUCUGACAAGCCUGCUCCAACUACACCUAAGGAGACUGCUCCAACUACCCCCAAGGAGCCUGCACCCACUACCCCCAAGAAGCCUGCUCCAACUACUCCUGAGACACCUCCUCCAACCACUUCAGAGGUCUCUACUCCAACUACCACCAAGGAGCCUACCACUAUCCACAAAAGCCCUGAUGAAUCAACUCCUGAGCUUUCUGCAGAACCCACACCAAAAGCUCUUGAAAACAGUCCCAAGGAACCUGGUGUACCUACAACUAAGACUCCUGCAGCGACUAAACCUGAAAUGACUACAACAGCUAAAGACAAGACAACAGAAAGAGACUUACGUACUACACCUGAAACUACAACUGCUGCACCUAAGAUGACAAAAGAGACAGCAACUACAACAGAAAAAACUACCGAAUCCAAAAUAACAGCUACAACCACACAAGUAACAUCUACCACAACUCAAGAUACCACACCAUUCAAAAUUACUACUCUUAAAACAACUACUCUUGCACCCAAAGUAACUACAACAAAAAAGACAAUUACUACCACUGAGAUUAUGAACAAACCUGAAGAAACAGCUAAACCAAAAGACAGAGCUACUAAUUCUAAAGCGACAACUCCUAAACCUCAAAAGCCAACCAAAGCACCCAAAAAACCCACUUCUACCAAAAAGCCAAAAACAAUGCCUAGAGUGAGAAAACCAAAGACGACACCAACUCCCCGCAAGAUGACAUCAACAAUGCCAGAAUUGAACCCUACCUCAAGAAUAGCAGAAGCCAUGCUCCAAACCACCACCAGACCUAACCAAACUCCAAACUCCAAACUAGUUGAAGUAAAUCCAAAGAGUGAAGAUGCAGGUGGUGCUGAAGGAGAAACACCUCAUAUGCUUCUCAGGCCCCAUGUGUUCAUGCCUGAAGUUACUCCCGACAUGGAUUACUUACCGAGAGUACCCAAUCAAGGCAUUAUCAUCAAUCCCAUGCUUUCCGAUGAGACCAAUAUAUGCAAUGGUAAGCCAGUAGAUGGACUGACUACUUUGCGCAAUGGGACAUUAGUUGCAUUCCGAGGUCAUUAUUUCUGGAUGCUAAGUCCAUUCAGUCCACCAUCUCCAGCUCGCAGAAUUACUGAAGUUUGGGGUAUUCCUUCCCCCAUUGAUACUGUUUUUACUAGGUGCAACUGUGAAGGAAAAACUUUCUUCUUUAAGGAUUCUCAGUACUGGCGUUUUACCAAUGAUAUAAAAGAUGCAGGGUACCCCAAACCAAUUUUCAAAGGAUUUGGAGGACUAACUGGACAAAUAGUGGCAGCGCUUUCAACAGCUAAAUAUAAGAACUGGCCUGAAUCUGUGUAUUUUUUCAAGAGAGGUGGCAGCAUUCAGCAGUAUAUUUAUAAACAGGAACCUGUACAGAAGUGCCCUGGAAGAAGGCCUGCUCUAAAUUAUCCAGUGUAUGGAGAAACGACACAGGUUAGGAGACGUCGCUUUGAACGUGCUAUAGGACCUUCUCAAACACACACCAUCAGAAUUCAAUAUUCACCUGCCAGACUGGCUUAUCAAGACAAAGGUGUCCUUCAUAAUGAAGUUAAAGUGAGUAUACUGUGGAGAGGACUUCCAAAUGUGGUUACCUCAGCUAUAUCACUGCCCAACAUCAGAAAACCUGACGGCUAUGAUUACUAUGCCUUUUCUAAAGAUCAAUACUAUAACAUUGAUGUGCCUAGUAGAACAGCAAGAGCAAUUACUACUCGUUCUGGGCAGACCUUAUCCAAAGUCUGGUACAACUGUCCUUAGACUGAUGAGCAAAGGAGGAGUCAACUAAUGAAGAAAUGAAUAAUAAAUUUUGACACUGAAAAACAUUUUAUUAAUAAAGAAUAUUGACAUGAGUAUACCAGUUUAUAUAUAAAAAUGUUUUUAAACUUGACAAUCAUUACACUAAAACAGAUUUGAUAAUCUUAUUCACAGUUGUUAUUGUUUACAGACCAUUUAAUUAAUAUUUCCUCUGUUUAUUCCUCCUCUCCCUCCCAUUGCAUGGCUCACACCUGUAAAAGAAAAAAGAAUCAAAUUGAAUAUAUCUUUUAAGAAUUCAAAACUAGUGUAUUCACUUACCCUAGUUCAUUAUAAAAAAUAUCUAGGCAUUGUGGAUAUAAAACUGUUGGGUAUUCUACAACUUCAAUGGAAAUUAUUACAAGCAGAUUAAUCCCUCUUUUUGUGACACAAGUACAAUCUAAAAGUUAUAUUGGAAAACAUGGAAAUAUUAAAAUUUUACACUUUUACUAGCUAAAACAUAAUCACAAAGCUUUAUCGUGUUGUAUAAAAAAAUUAACAAUAUAAUGGCAAUAGGUAGAGAUACAACAAAUGAAUAUAACACUAUAACACUUCAUAUUUUCCAAAUCUUAAUUUGGAUUUAAGGAAGAAAUCAAUAAAUAUAAAAUAUAAGCACAUAUUUAUUAUAUAUCUAAGGUAUACAAAUCUGUCUACAUGAAGUUUACAGAUUGGUAAAUAUCACCUGCUCAACAUGUAAUUAUUUAAUAAAACUUUGGAACAUUAAAAAAAUAAAUUGGAGGCUUAAGGAUUAGAAAA